GGAGCCGACUUCCUCCUGGUCGGCGGCUGCAGCGGGGUGAGCGGCGGCAGCGGCCGGGGAUCCUGGAGCCAUGGGGCGCGCGCGCGACGCCAUCCUGGAUGCGCUGGAGAACCUGACCGCCGAGGAGCUCAAGAAGUUCAAGCUGAAGCUGCUGUCGGUGCCGCUGCGCGAGGGCUACGGGCGCAUCCCGCGGGGCGCGCUGCUGUCCAUGGACGCCUUGGACCUCACCGACAAGCUGGUCAGCUUCUACCUGGAGACCUACGGCGCCGAGCUCACCGCUAACGUGCUGCGCGACAUGGGCCUGCAGGAGAUGGCCGGGCAGCUGCAGGCGGCCACGCACCAGGGCUCUGGAGCCGCGCCAGCUGGGAUCCAGGCCCCUCCUCAGUCGGCAGCCAAGCCAGGCCUGCACUUUAUAGACCAGCACCGGGCUGCGCUUAUCGCGAGGGUCACAAACGUUGAGUGGCUGCUGGAUGCUCUGUACGGGAAGGUCCUGACGGAUGAGCAGUACCAGGCAGUGCGGGCCGAGCCCACCAACCCAAGCAAGAUGCGGAAGCUCUUCAGUUUCACACCAGCCUGGAACUGGACCUGCAAGGACUUGCUCCUCCAGGCCCUAAGGGAGUCCCAGUCCUACCUGGUGGAGGACCUGGAGCGGAGCUGAGGCUCCUUCCCAGCAACACUCCGGUCAGCCCCUGGCAAUCCCACCAAAUCAUCCUGAAUCUGAUCUUUUUAUACACAAUAUACGAAAAGCCAGCUUGAA